CUCUUUCCCUCCGCGCUGCCUCUCCGAGGUCCUCCCGCCGAGCCCCGGCGCGGGGCAUGAGGAGCCCCCGGGUGCCGCCCAGAGACCAGCAGGCUGCGCGCACACCUAGCCAGCGGCAGACGGGGACAUGAGCAGCGCGCACGGGGUCCCGCGCCCGGCGGCCAGCCCUAUCCGGCGGCGGCCAGCGGGUCAACGCUGCCCGGGAGAAUGAGGCAGGAGCCGGCGGCAGCCUCCUUUUUUUCCUUCUCCUCGCCUUCCUGCGGCUCCGGCGCUCCGGGUCCGGGCCGGGCUGCGGCUCUGCUGCGUGCCCCGCGCGCCCCUCAACCGCCUCCGGAUGCGCUUCUCGAUCUCAGCCCGCUGUCGCCUUCUCUCUGACCCUGGUCCCUUCCACUGCAGGCUGUUGCUCCGGUGUCUCUGGGCUGCUCCACCACGUGGUGCCUGCCCAUCAUGGCAUCCACCACCAGGUGGCCUUUUUCUUGGUUAGCCUGGCAAGGAAGAUAAAGACAUUUGCAACCAAGAUGGUAAUCACUAGUGAAAAUGAUGAAGACAGAGGAGGUCAAGAAAAAGAAAGUAAAGAGGAGAGUGUCUUGGCAAUGCUGGGGAUUAUCGGGACCAUUCUGAACCUGAUUGUGAUCAUAUUUGUCUACAUAUACACCACCCUGUGAAUGGCCCAGAGCGUCCUCAGAGGCCUCAGAAUGGCCAAAGACGGAAGUCCUGCGUGUCGGCGCAUCACUGACCAGACCCUGCGAGAACAAGCAGGCUUGACCCGCACAUACCACCCAAUCAAAUGCACCUUCAAACUUUACAAAAGGUCACACAAAUAGACCGAUCCUGCUGCAGGGAGCAGACACUAAAGCACAAUGAUUCCAACAAAACUCAUUCACAGCACUAGGAACUCAACGUCUUUGGCAGGGGGCCCAGAAGAAUGCUUGGAAGACCAGCCUCUGACACCAUCAGUGAGCGGAUGGGUGCAGAAAUUCAUUAUUCCAGAUCGCUGACAGAUAUCACAUAUUUGAAAAGAUGAAUAGGGCGGACAUGGCUCAGAUGUGUGUCUCCCAGGACAAGUGUUUCAUCUUCACUUGACGAGCUAUUUAGUGGAAAAACCACAGGCGCAGCCCUUUGACAGGCAUCCCAUUCAUCAAAAGUGUCUAACUAUUUGAUACUGGGGAGAUAACUUAUUUUUCUUUUUUCAUUGGCUUGACAUGUGUAUCUGUUCAUGUCAAGGUUUAUAAAUAUAUAUUUUUAAUAAAUGUGCUCUAUUUUUUAGCAUGAACCAAAUACUUGGAGAGGCACUCCCAGAUCCAUAGAGCUUUCCUUAGUUUUAUCUGCUUUGUCCCCUCCUCCCCCAACUACAGAUGUUCUGUUGUGGAGCCAUUCUAGUCCUUUUGUCUCAUCUUGAGUCUUUUACCUUGCGCUUUUGUUCUCUCUCUCUCCUCUCUCUCUGCCUCUUUGGUCUGAAGGACAUUUUCCCAUACUGUCAGCCAUGGUUUUGGGUGCAUGUUUUAAGAUUGUCCAUUGAGUGGCUUUUUGUUGUUAUCUCGGAGAUAUAAAAUGAUUGUGGGCAUGCAGACCUUAGAUGCACCCUAUCUUUACUGAGAAUUAUGCAUGAAUAAGGGCUGAGUGAUAGAUCAGCUUAAAAUUAAAAGGACUACCUUUGAGGAAGAAGAGCGUGGCUAUAUUUGCAGAUGAACUUUUGAACAGAAUAUUCAGCUUCUUACCGGCAGCGUUAUUGUUUCAUUCUUGUGACCAUUCGUUUAUCAGAUUUUGAUUUUAGCGGUCAUGUACCGCGAGAGUUGGGAAGAACAAGGGGGAAAGCUCGGGAUUAGGUGCAUUACUCCUUCCUUUGCAAGAUACCUGGGAUCCUCCUCAAAAGCGGGUGGGGUAUAAAUGACACAAGAACUCCCCCAGGAGAUCUCAUGGUGAUUCAGGCUGUGAGGACAGCCCUGUGACAGGUGACUUUUCAGGGACAUGAGGAGGGGAUUUAAUGAUUGCCCUAAAGGACUUCUGUAUUUUUAAAGCCCCUGGUUUACACCCACAUGAAGCUAUUUCCUCUCUGGCAGGGAUGGUUGCAUAAAAACAAAUUAGCUCCCUUCUGGCUCCCUGAAAUGGGCCCUUGCCUGGCUACAGUGGCAUGGCCUUAAAGAGAGGGUUAGUAUUCCUUCUGCCAUUGCCAGCUGUAUUAGUCUGUUUUCACACUGCUGAAAAAGACAUCCCCAAGACUGGGCAAUUUACAAAGAAAGAGGUUUAUUGGACUUACAGUUCCACGUGGCUGAGGAGGCCUCACAAUUACGGUGGAAGGUGAAAGGCACGUCUCACAUGGUGGCAGACAAGAGAAGUGAACAUGUGCAAGGAGACUCCCAUUUUUAAAACAGAUCUCGUGAGACUUUUUCACUAUCAUGCAAACAGCAUGGGAAACCUGCCCCCGUGAUUCAGUUACCUCCCACCGGGUCCCUCCCACAACACAUGGGUAUUCAAGAUGAGAUUUGGGUGGGGUUACAGCCAAACUCUAUCACCAGCCUUGCCCCUGGGCAGAAGCAGCAGCAGUCUGCCUGGCUGGAUUCAAAUGAUUCUGAGGCUUCUAUAGUCUAUGCCUGCAGAUCUCUCCCUCACCCAUGCUAUAGUGUCUGAAAUUCCACCAUUAGAGAGUCAUUUCUUGGGCUCUGUUAAAUGGACCAGGCUCUUUUAUAAAGAAAAUGCCCCUGAGCAGCUGGCUCUGGCAUUGAUUUAUGAUAUCUUCUCUUCCCUGCCAGAAGGAAGGAAGCUAAGGUGCAUGUAGGGCGUACUGUGUGCCCAGGCACUGUGCCAGAUGCUUUGGAUACUUGGAGUCAUUGAAUUCUUGUAGUAACCCUGUGAGAGAGGGAGUCUUUUCUCCACAUUGUAGAAGAAGGAAAAAGGGCUCAGAGAGGUCAAGAAAUGUCCCUGAGAUCACAUGGCUUCUAGUGGAGUCAAGAUCCAAACCCAAUGUGUCUGAUUCCUUAGCCCUUGGGGGUCCGGAGGCUGCUGAACAAGAAAGGAGGUGGAGAGGAGAGAAAGCUGCAGGCAUACCACCGCACACCCUUCUCCCUCCCCUGUAAAAACAACCCUGGGAACUCCCUGGACACUAGCAGAAUAUCAUACACUAAGGAUAAGGGAUGAGAGGAGGCUGGUUAGAAAUAAAGCAGUGUCAGGGGGAAGGAGCUACUCAGUAGGCUCUGUGUGAUUCUAGAAAGACUGUAUGAAAAUUCUGAACAGUGAACAGAAUAAACAAUAAAGGUGCAAUGGAAAAAAAUA